ACUUCCGGAAUCUCUCGGCGUGUGAGCUUGGUUGUCCUACCAAAGCCAGCGUUUCGGCUCGCGUGCGCCGGCCUAGUUUGCUCGCGUCCUCACGCGCUUUGGGUUUCCCGGUCUCAUGGCCGGCCUGACCUUAUUUGUGGGCCGCCUCCCGCCCUCGGCCCGCAGUGAGCAGCUGGAGGAACUGUUCAGUCAGGUGGGGCCGGUGAAGCAGUGCUUCGUGGUGACUGAAAAAGGGAGUAAGGCAUGUCGAGGCUUUGGCUAUGUCACUUUUUCAAUGCUGGAAGAUGUUCAGAGGGCCCUCAAGGAGAUUACCACCUUUGAAGGUUGCAAGAUCAACGUGACUGUUGCCAAGAAAAAACUGAGGAACAAGACAAAGGAAAAGGGGAAAAAUGAAAACUCAGAGUGCCCAAAGAAGGAGCCGAAGGCUAAAAAAGCCAAAGUGGCAGAUAAGAAAGCCAGAUUAAUUAUUCGGAACCUGAGCUUUAAGUGUUCAGAAGAUGACUUGAAGACAGUAUUUGCUCAAUUUGGAGCUGUCCUGGAAGUAAAUAUCCCUAGGAAACCAGAUGGGAAGAUGCGCGGUUUUGGUUUUGUUCAGUUCAAAAACCUCCUAGAAGCAGGUAAAGCUCUCAAAGGCAUGAACAUGAAAGAGAUAAAAGGCCGGACAGUGGCUGUGGAUUGGGCCGUGGCAAAGGAUAAAUAUAAAGAUACACAGUCUGUUUCUGCUAUAGGUGAGGAAAAGAGCCAUGAAUCUAAACAUCAGGAAUCAGUUAAAAAGAAGGGCAGAGAGGAAGAGGAUAUGGAAGAGGAAGAAAACGAUGAUGAUGACGAUGAUGAUGAUGAAGAAGAUGGGGUUUUUGAUGAUGAAGAUGAAGAGGAAGAGAAUAUAGAAUCAAAGGUGACCAAGCCUGUGCAAAUUCAGAAGAGAGCAGUCAAGAGACCAGCCCCUGCAAAAAGCAGUGAUCAUUCUGAGGAGGACAGUGACCUAGAGGAAAGCGAUAGUAUUGAUGAUGGAGAGGAACUGGCUCAGAGUGAUACCAGCACUGAGGAGCAAGAGGAUAAAGCUGUGCAAGUCUCAAACAAAAAGAAGAGGAAAUUACCCUCUGAUGUGAAUGAAGGGAAAACUGUUUUUAUCAGAAAUCUGUCCUUUGACUCAGAAGAAGAAGAACUUGGGGAGCUUCUCCAACAGUUUGGAGAACUCAAAUAUGUCCGCAUUGUCUUGCAUCCAGACACAGAGCAUUCUAAAGGUUGUGCAUUUGCCCAGUUCAUGACUCAAGAAGCAGCUCAGAAAUGCCUUCUAGCUGCUUCUCCAGAGAAUGAGGCUGGUGGGCUUAAACUGGAUGGCCGGCAGCUCAAGGUUGACUUGGCGGUGACCCGUGAUGAGGCUGCAAAGCUUCAGACGACGAAGGUGAAGAAGCCGACUGGCACCCGGAAUCUCUAUCUGGCCCGAGAAGGCUUGAUUCGUGCUGGGACGAAGGCUGCAGAGGGUGUGAGUGCUGCUGAUAUGGCCAAAAGAGAACGGUUUGAGCUGCUGAAGCAUCAGAAACUCAAGGACCAGAAUAUCUUUGUCUCCCGAACCAGGCUCUGCCUGCACAAUCUCCCAAAGGCUGUAGAUGACAAACAGCUCAGAAAGCUGCUGCUGAGUGCUACUAGUGGAGAGAAAGGGGUGCGCAUCAAGGAGUGUAGAGUGAUGCGAGACCUCAAAGGAGUUCAUGGGAACAUGAAGGGUCAGUCCCUGGGCUACGCCUUUGCGGAGUUCCAAGAGCACGAGCAUGCCCUGAAAGCCCUCCGCCUCAUCAACAACAAUCCAGAAAUCUUUGGGCCUCUGAAGAGACCAAUAGUGGAGUUCUCUUUAGAAGAUCGAAGAAAACUUAAAAUGAAGGAAUUAAGGAUCCAGCGCAGCUUGCAAAAAAUGAGAUCCAAGCCUGCAACUGGUGAGCCUCAGAAGGGGCAACCAGAGCCUGCAAAAGACCAGCAACAGAAGGCAGCUCAACACCACACAGAGGAACAAAGCAAGGUGCCCCCAGAGCAGAAGAGAAAGGCGGGCUCUACCUCAUGGACCGGGUUCCAGACCAAGGCUGAAGUGGAGCAGGUGGAGCUGCCUGAUGGAAAGAAGAGAAGAAAGGUCCUGGCGCUCCCCUCACACCGAGGCCCCAAAAUCAGGUUGCGGGACAAAGGCAAAGUGAAGCCCGUCCAUCCCAAAAAGCCAAAGCCACAGAUAAACCAGUGGAAGCAGGAGAAGCAGCAAUUAUCGUCCGAGCAGGUAUCUAGGAAAAAAGCUAAGGGAAAUAAGACGGAAACCCGCUUCAACCAGCUGGUCGAACAAUAUAAGCAGAAAUUAUUGGGACCUUCUAAAGGAGCACCUCUUGCAAAGAGGAGCAAAUGGUUUGAUAGUUGAUGAUGGCAGCAGGCUGGGUAAGAAGCUGGGUUGUGUACUUUCUGGUGACACUCCUGGGCUCCUCCCCAUCCCCCGUGUCUCUCACUGAGGGAAAGAAAAUCCCCAAGGGCACUGCCACUGUGCUCGGAGGUGCCCUGGACUGUGUACAUCUGAACUUUGGUCCAUCCUUUGAUGUGUGGUUCGUUAGCCACAAAGAGAAAUAUCUGAAAGUCAACAUGAUGCUUCUUGCAUAUUAUCCAGAUUAUUGUAUGAAGUUGUGUCUAUAAUUAUUACCAAUUUUUAUUCUUUAUUUCUCAAAUGGAAACACCUGAAAAAGCAUUCUGGAGUGCUGAAUUUUUAAGAUGUAUAUUUUGUUAAGCAUAUUCUCUAAAUGAGAUAUUGUGUGGCUUUUUAGUAACAACGUCAUUUCUAAUAUGUGUGACUCCUUUAUUAUGUAUGAACAUUCUUUGACAUUCCUAAUUCAGCUCUGUAGUCUUACACACUGCAGGAACUGUCUAAGCGAGAGCAGAGAGAAAUGCUUUCUAACCUAAUCGCUGCAGGCGGAGACACUUGGAAAAGAAUGGGGGGAGGUGGGGCCUGACAGAGAGCAGCACUUAUGUGUUUGUCAGAUGAGGGGAUUUCCAGUUGAAUUGGCCUGCAGUGGCCUAAAGACACUAGCCUGGUUAGCGAUGACCUGCAUUUCUCUCAUAGAGCACCUCCCUUUUCAUCGUAUCCACUAGCUCUCUAAGUCCUCCUUAAUGAGGACACUUGAUCCUCAUUAAGUCUGCCCCUUAAGAUGGCUUCACACCUACUGAAAAACUCCAGGGGUUUGACAUCUCACUUUGAUUGAAAUCUUGUCUUCCUAUAACAUUUGAUUCCCUGGGCUCUUCAGCCCUAUCACCUCUGCUUGUCUUUAUCCACUCUCUUCUUCAUUCACUUUUGGCUACACAGGCCUUCCUUCCAUCUCUUGACUCUUGACCACCUCAGAGCCUUUGUAUCCGUUCCCUUUGCCUGGAGAGUUUUUCCCUUGCAUCUUUUACUUGUCACUCAGAUCUCCACUAGUUGUCGCCUCCUCCUGGAGCUCUUCCCAGACUAUCUAAAGUAGGGCUUUUCUUCCCCUCCCCUCUAUCUUGCCCCCUUACUGAAAUCUGCUUCCCUGUUUCUUCUUCUUUUUUUUUUUUUUUUGAGAUGGAGUCUCACUCUGUCGCCCAGGCUGGAGUGCAAUGGCGCUGUCUCAGCUCAUUGCAACCUCCACCUCCCGGGUUCAAGCGACUUUCCCGCCUCACCCUCCCAAGUAGCUGGGACUACAGGUGCACGCCACCAUUCUUGGCUAAAUUUUGUAUUUUUAGUAGAGAUGGGGUUUCACCAUGUUGACUAGGCUGGUCUUGAACUCCUGACCUCAGGUGAUCCGCCCACCUCGACCUCCCAAAGUCCUGGUAUUACAGGCGUGAGCCACCACGCCUGGCCUGCUUCCCUGUUUCUUUCUAGCACUAAUCUCUAUCUGAAAUCAUUUGUCUCUUUCUAGCACUAAUCUCUAUCUGAAAUUGUUUGUCUCUCCAGUUAGAAUGUAUGCUUUGUGAGAGGGACUUUAUCCCUCUUGUUCACUCCUGUAGACACAGCACCUAGUACUGACCCAGGCACGUAGUAAGUAUUGAAUAAAUAUUUGUUGAAUGAAAAAAAUAAGGUAGGAAAGGAAGAAACAGUAUUCAGUAGGCAAGAGAAAAAGUUGAGAACGUGGCCCAAAAUUCUUGAUUGCUUAGUCUAGUUGAGUGUUACAAAUAAUGCUUUGACAGAACCAUUGCUGAGCUAGAGAUAUGGUUAUUUCUUUUUUUUUUUUUUUUUUGAGACAGUCUUGCUCUGUUGCCCAGGCUGGAGUGCAAUGGCAUGAUCUUGGCUCACUGCAACCUCCGCCUCCUGGGUUCAAGCGAUUCUCCUGCCUCAGCCUCCCGAGUAGCGGGGAUUACAGGUGCUGCCACCACGCCCGGCUAAUUUUUGUAUUUUUAGUAGAGACGGGUUUUCACCAUGUUGGCCAGGCUGAUCUCAAACUCCUGACCUUGUGAUCUGCCCACCUCAGCCUCCUGAAGUGCUGGGAUUACAGGCAUGAGCCUGGUUGAGACAUGGUUAUUUCAUCGCAAUAUCUUGGGGAACCCAUGAAUGCUCUGAAAUGCCUUUGGUUUAGAAAUGGAUGAAGGAGAGGCCAUGGAAAUAUUUAGACCUUUUGGAGAGAUCGAAAGGACAGGUGAUUUAUCUCCAAGUUCACCUCGAGACAUGACUUGGGCUGUCAAAUGUUCUUACGGUAGCCUGGCAACAUGUCUUUCUCAGCCUGGUCUGUACAGUGUGGAGGAAGUAAGGGACUUUAUUAAGAGUGUCACAAUAGCUAUAACCUGCCAGUCAGGUGAUCUGUUUUUCCUUGGCCAUCUCUCCGUCUGCUCACCACUCUUUUUUCCCUAGUACACGAAUAUCUUUAACAUUCAAAAAUAUAUCUUAACACUUAGGAUAGAUCAAAAUUGGUGUUCAUUCAGAUAACAUUGUCAGAUUCUCUUAGAUCCAAAUAUUUCUUUUAACAACUUAACAGUAUGUUAAAACCUCAUUCACUUGCUUGGAGAGCUGUUGUACAGUUCUUUAAAGAGUUCUUUAUAUGAGGUUGAAUCUUCCCUUUCUUAAUAGUCAAAUUCUAUAUAUGGUGUCUUCCUUUGGAACACCUUACCAUGGGCUAUUUGGUCAGCUCCAUUGACUCCUUGCCUUGGGAAUUUUAGUGCAGUGAGAGUUGUGCUCACUUCUCCUUCACUUCAGGGCCUGAUGUGUCAGGAAAUGGAGUUUUCUGAAUUAACAUGAAAGUUGAGUUGCAGAUUGCUUGGUUAAAAAACAACAGGUGGGGCACAGAGUCUCAUACCUAUGAUUGCAGCACUUCGGGAGGUGGGAGGAUUGCUUGAGGUCAGGAGUUUGAGACCGACCUGGCCAACAUAGUGAGACCCCCAUCUCUAUUAUUUUGAAAAACAACAGCAAAUUUUUUCUUAACAUCCAAGACAAGGCCACCAGUCAAAACUAUCAAGUUUUAGUAGUAUUUUCCUGCUUGAUUAUAUAAUAGCCUGGCUUAGAGAUACAACCUUUAAAUAAGGAAUCUUAAGAUGAUGUGCAGCUGUUCUUUGCCUUAUUUGUUUGUUUGUUGGUUAGUUUGUAGUUUCUAAGAAUCUGCUCUGUUCAGCUGUACAGUUCCUUCUUCUGGAGUUAACCUGUGGCAAGGAUUAUGUUUCACCUGUCACAAAAAUGAGAUCUGUGCCUUCCUCUAUUAUAAAGUUAGGGCAUGUGAUUCAUUCUUCGAAAUACUUCAAAAUGUACUUUGGUAUGUUUUUGUCUUGAAAAGAGGUUUUCUAGCUAGAAAUUCGGGGCCCAGAAGGUCAAGGCUCCAGAGAUCCCCUUCUCAUCAUCCUUCAGUUGUCUGAGGAGACAGAGGAUCACAUGUGUCACAGUGAGUGCUGAUUCCCCAGAAUCUGCAGUCUUAAGCUCCCCUGCUGACGCACACAGCCAGUUCUCUGCUUCAUAUUCAUGUGACCCACUGUGAAGUGACAGGCAGCUGCCAAUUCUGUCAUAUAAGAAGCAGCUCUGCCCAUGCAACUUUGAAAGUUCCUGCACUUCUCCAUAGACUGCUCCUUCAUGGAAAUAAACACAUCAUCACACUGUGGGUGCCUAAGCUAAGUUUGUUUGCAGUUUGAUGAUGCCCAGCUCCUUUUCAACUCAGCCUUAAUUGGCACUUUAAGGGCCAGGAUGAGGUUUCUCUCAGGCCAAGUCGAGAUUUCCAGAUUUCCUUUUGUCCAAGGCUGACCAGUUUAGAAGUUAUUCACAUCCUUGUUUUAGUUCUUUCCUUCUUGUCCUGGUACCUCUUCCUUUCCAGGAUUAUUUGCAGAGUCUGUGAUGGCUUACUUGGUGACCAGACAUGGGGUGAGCUACUGGUAUAGUCUGAUUACUUUGGCAUCUAUUCUGAACUGGUCAUUGGCUGUACAUGAGUUUUUGUGCUGGUAAAGGAAUAUACUGGGAAGAUUGGAAGGCACAGACUGGGAACUAAUUCUGAGAAGAGAACUGCUGAGUUACUGAAAGACCUUUUGGACCACCCCUAAAUGGAGCAUCUUGAUAGAUGGCAAAUCCAGUGUUUCUUAAACUUGUCCAUGCUGCCCAGAGCCCACUGCCUUUUAUCAGAUGUGAGACUUCACUGCCACAGUGUCAUCCCACAGUUUCCUUCCCUGGACAUUUGAUAAAGGGAAAAUCAUUUCUUGUCCUUUAAGGCAGGGACUAUUAUUUUUUCACUUUUCCACAUACCCCACAACACCUAACAUUGAUUUACUCGUAGUAGGAGUUUCAUACUGUUGAACUCUCUAAAGGCCAUUUGUUCCAGGGCCUAGCUGGGCUUGUGAAGGACAACAGAGUCAUUUCCUAAGGACCCCAAAAGACAGCAUGAAGGAAAAAAUAAUAAUAAACUGCUGUUCACAGUGCCUUGAGUGUACCACCGUACUUUCUGCUAUGCCUUGUCCAUUCCAAUCUGGACAGUCUCUGUGCCCCUCCUUUCCACUCAAGUGUUAUCCAGCACUCAAGUUCUGGCUCAAGGCCCAACAUCUCCGUGGGGACCUCAGCCAUCCCAGGGCAUUGUGACCCCUUCCUCUAAGUCCCCGGCACACUCGCUGAUUGGUACCCUCUCAUUCGACAAAGCAUAUGCCAUUGUGGCUUACUUGUCAUUUCUUUAGGUCUUGCCUUCCCAAGUAGAUCAUGAGCCACUAUAAGAACUAGCUCCCAUAGUCCCAGCCCCUGGGCCUGGUACAUGGCAAUGCUUAGUGAUUGGUGAUUGAGGAUAAUGGUGGUAAAGGAUGUACCAGACAGUCAUCUCCUGAAGAGAUGCCGAACAACCUGUCCUUGUUUUAUGUAUUUUCUCUUUCUUUCCUGUCCAGUUUUAUUCCUCUCAUAGUAACUGCUAAAAAAAUAUCAGUUCCUGUCACUCUUCCACCCCUUUUCUCCCUCUCCCCUGCAUUGUGGUCUGGGCCUUGGUCCACUAGCAACUCCCCUUAGGUGUUGCUUAAUCUGCCUCAUGGCCAAAGCCAAUCCCAUUCCUGUCCCCCGCUACCCAAGGGACUCCCAGUCUGUAUGCACAAGGCGGGAUGUGAAGUCUGGAUGUGCAAGAAACCCAGCUGUAAGAAACAGCUUCCCUCGGCUUGGCAUGGUGGCUCAUGCCUAUAUUCCCAGCACUUUGAGAGGUCAAAGUGGGAGAAUCACUUGAGCCCAGGAGUUCAGGACUAGCCUGGGCAACAUAGCAAGAUCCCACCUCUACAAAAAAAGAAAAAAUUCAGAGUCUCAAAUGUCCCUUCAUCUCCUUACUCUCGACCUGUCUCCCUAGUUCUCUGCCGCCUUUUCCUCUCCCCUGGAUCUGACACUCAAUUGUCUGCAUGCACUUUUCAACUGAAAGAGACUCCAAUGCCAUCCUUCUGAUGAAAUUUUUGCUUUGGAUACUACUGCAGAAAAAAUGCUAUCUUGUAUUCUGGUCCAUGGUGGGGAAGACCCUGUCGUAGAACCUGGCAACUCAAGUGGAGGGAGGGGCCAGAACAUUGUUCUUAUGCUAUUUACAGUGAGACAACAGGAUUGAUGCAGAACUUUCUUUUUUUUUUUUUUUUUUUGAGACAGAGUUUCAUUCUUGUUGCCCAGGGCUGGAGUGCAGUGGCAUGAUCUCAGCUCACUGCAACCUCCACCCCCCAGGUUCAAGCAGUUCUUCCUCAGCCUCCGGAGUAGCUGGGAUUACAGGCGUGCGCCACCACGCCCCACUAAUUUUUGUAUUUUUGGUAGAGACGGGGUUUCACCAGUGUUGGCCAGGCUGGUCUCGAACUCCUGACCUCAGGUGAUCCACCCACCUCGGCCUCCCAAAGUGCUGGGAUUACAGGCAUGAACCACCGUGCCCGGCCGUGAUGCGCAACUUUCUAAUAACAUACUUUUGAAAGUGCCCAGACAUACAUCCCUCCUCUGGUACCACAGUGGCCAUCAGUUGCCAGAGAACAUGAAAUUAUCCAGCCCUCAGCUCUGCAGCAGGAUUCUGAGGAGUAAAGCAGGCCUGUAAAGUACUCUAAAGUACUUCAGAGAGGUAAUGCCACAAAGCGAAGAACACCUCUUGGAGGCAGAGCCCCUCAGCCCUAUCCAGGCCAGCAGUGUCCACUUGAAAUCUGAAAGCAGCCUCCCUCACCAAACCAGCAAGAUGGAAAACCUCCCUGGGUUGGCAAGUGGCCCUGGGAAGUACAUGCCCCAUCUCUGUCAGGAUAGCAGUGGAGAGGUUUCGUGCCAGUGCCAGCUCCACCCACCCAGAUGGUACUCAAGACUCCAAGCCUGUCAAUGGGGUGGAAACUUUCUGGCAUUUUCUGUCAGAAGGGUGAGUUAGCACUGAACCAUCUCAUGUGUCUUUUCACUGAGUAACAGCCCAUAUCCAUUCCAUGAAAUGAGUGACUGCUUUGUUGAAUCAGAUAGUAACAAACAUUUAUUUGUAGUCUGGUUGUGUCAUAUCAUGGUUGAAUUGCAAACAGGUUGGAUAGAAGAGUCAGCAAAAAUCAACAAAAGCAUUCUGUAAAAAACUUUUCUAGAAUUACAAUAAAUGGCAUUGUAUAUUUUAUUUAUAAAUUAUGUGCUGCACAUCAUUUUUAUCAAUGAAAUUUAUAAUAAAUUUCUGUACAUAUAUACAUUUUUAUCCCAGAGAGCCAGUUGUUAAGCAUUUACCAGCAAUAAAUGCUUUUUGUUUCCUGCUUACACAGGUUCUGGGAGUGGCCAGCCCACUCUUUGAGAUGUCCCCACUUGCUUUUUUAGUUGUCCAAGUAGUGUUCUGCCCAGCCUUCCCGACUCUCUUUCUUAUCCUUCCCUCGAAACUAUUCUGUUCCUUAUGCUUAAAUACUUUCCAGUCAUGGGAGCUUUGCUGUAGGCCCUUGGCCUUUCAUGGGUAGCUUCUGAUACGUGCAUGGGUGUUAAUAGAGGAAGUUGACCCCGCCUGGGAAGAAUAAUGACCUAUGGAGACCUGGCCCUUUCUCUUAUGGCUUCUUAAAGUGACAGCUGUUAUGGGAAGUUCAGGCAUCUUGACGUGGAAAAUACAUUGUUCAUUUUCUUUUAAUUUUUUUUCCCCUAACCACUAUACCAACAGGGAUGGAAAGAUACUUUUAGUUGGAAGGAAUUUGGAGCCCUUAAACGACACCUGGAGCAGCUGCCUGUGGGUGGGGCUUUGCACAGUCUCAUCCUGGCAAGGGAGGACGAGCCAAGGACCAGUUUUGCAGAAUUGUCAUCAUGAGGCCCUGGUUGUGUGCUGGGCUGGGGCAUUGCCCCUUUCCAGGAGGCCAGGCCAAGCAGGGCUGCCUGGCUUAGGCUUUUGCAUCUUCAGCAUCCUUUCACGUCUCUUAUCUCAGGUGACCUUCACAGCAAGCCUGGUGAAGGUUAUUGAGAAGCAGAUGUCACCACCUAGUCUUAGAGCUGAUGAAAGCAGGAUGUGGGGAAGUCCAGACCCUCUCCUGAAACCCCUUGGCCACCUGAGCUAGUACCAGAGCAAGGUCCCACUUGGCCGUGAGUGCUGUCUCUAGGGCCUAUUUCAGGAACUGUCUCAUAUAUAAGAACAGAACACUUUUUGCCAGCUAUACCAAAUGUUUUUGGGAUUAAAAAAAUAGUUUCUCUUUUCCAAAUUAGGUGGUAAGAAAAGGAAGGGCAUUUUCAUUCUCACAUUCUUUGAAUGUUGAAACGUUUUAAAAACUUCCAGCUGGGCUUGGUGGCUCAUACCUGUAACCCCAGCACUAUGGGAGGCUGAGAUGGGAGGAUCCCUUGAGGCCAGGAGUUCAGGACCAGCCUGGGCAACAUAGUAAAACUGCCCAAAAUUUGAAAAUUAGCCUUGUGUGGUGGUGUGCACUGUAGUCCCAGCUGCUCGGGAGGCUGGGGCAGGAGGAUUGCUUGAGCCCAGGAGUUUGAGGCUGCAGUGAGCUAUGGUUGUACCACUGUACUCCAACCUGGGCAACAGCGUGAUACCCUGUCUAAAAAAAUAAUAAAAAUAAAAAAGGAUUAAACCCUUUACUUGACCAGCUUCUUUUCCUGCUACCCCUGGACUAACUAAUCAUUACAUAUUUUUGUAGUUGUUUUUUCUUUCUUUCUCUCUCCUGAUCUACCACAAGCCAAAUGUACUCAUAUACAUACUAAUAGGUGAAAAAAGAGAGUCUGAGGAGUGAAUACAUUUAUUUUGUGAUUUCCUAGGCAGUAGCUAGGACUCCCUUAGAGGUUGCUAAUAGGGAAAGGGUGCGCUGGCUCUACUCAGUUUUAUAACUGCUUUUCCCCGAAUUCUGCAGACAUCUUCAUUCCCCUGGAGGUCAGAUAAUGGCUAUUUAUUUUCCAUAGCCAUGAAAAUCUCUGGGGAGAGCUGUGGCAAUUUGACGAGAGCUAUUAAAGGGACAUUAGGAUUGAAGUAGCUGCUCAGGCAGUCACAUACCCUCGAUCCUCAUCUGCAGGGACAGCUGCCAGAACGAAUGAGCCCAGCUCUCCUGCCCGCAGCCAGCCGCGUGUGGGUGCAACUGGCGACCAGCCACUGGAGUGAGUCCCAGGGAAGGGGACAGGUUCUUAGAAUCACCAUUUGUCUCUGCUCUCUCCCUCUCUGCAAUAGGACGGGCACUCUAAACUCACAUAAUGGUUAAUAACAACAGCUAACAAUUACUGAGCACCUACUAUGUGUCAGGCAUGUGCUGAGGAUGAUCGCAUCAAGUAAAAUGCCUGUCUCUGGCCCAGAGGCCCAGAAGAAGAGAAAGAAGGGAAAUCUGUAGGAGGCAAACAGUCCCUUACCCCUCUGCUUGCAGACCUUCAGUGACAGGACACUCCCUGUUUGCUCCAAGCACCUCUUGCAUUUUCAGAGCUUGGGACACAGAUUCAGGGACUUGCACUUCGAUAGAGUGCCUCAGGACCCCUCGUCGGAGCCAUGGAAAGUCAGUUUCUGGGCCCAUCCUUCCUGUGGGGGUGUCUUUCCUUCUCUUGGCCACCCCCUAGGAAUCCCUAGUAGAGAGCAGGCACUUAAUAGCCAGUGCAGUGAGAGUGGUCUGUGAUGUCUGGGCCAGGGCAAGGCCCGCCAAGUGGGCUCCCAGGUGCCUGCCACAGAGCCUCUGGGGUUUGAGGCCCUCAGUGACCCUUAGGCAAUAGCUGGGUCUUAAUGAGGGAUCAUGUCCUUUCCUGGGUAGUCGUGGGUAGAGGGGUGUGAACUGAUCUGAGCUACUCUAGGAAGGCUAGAGACAAAAGCAGGAACCAAGAGAAGGGCUGAGGCUCCUUCCAAGAGACUCCAAGUCCUGAGGGCAAGAAGCGGAGAGCCUUGUGCCAGGCCAGGUGUUGCCCCUGUCAGUGCUGACGGACAGGCAAGAGAGGCUGCUGAUGCUGCAGCCCUGUGAAGCUGAGACUCACCCUUUGCCCACUUUCACAGCCAUCUCCCCAGGAGGCUGUGGUGACACAGGUAAAAGCCAAAGGACAGAGGAUGACCCUGGACAAAUCACUCAGACCCUCCAGUCCUCUUUGCUCAUUUAUAAAAUACAGGCAAAAAGCCCCCUAGUACUAAAUGAAAUAGCCACUGUAAAAGAGCACGGGAGAUAGGGUCUGUGAUGUCUUUUGUCCCCAGUGUCCUGAGUGAAUUCACAGGAAAGGGGAGAAAGACUGGUUGCCCACUUCCAGGGUGAUUGGCUAAUUUCCACUUCUUUCCUGCUAGGGAUGGGAACACACGCCAGAAUCCUGGGAAGGCUACAUGUCCUCAGGUGGUGCUGGCCCCACCUCCAGCCUCUGCAGGGAUACCAGGAUAUGAGCCAGGCUCUGCUCCCGGGGUGACCCAUCCUCCUCAGUGCCCCUUCUUUCCUCACAACUGCAGGCAGAAGGAGAGUGUGUCCUGUCUCUCUGAGGAGCUGGCUGUGCCAUUUAAGCAGGCCCUAGGGGUGGAGCGCUGUGAAGAGAUGGCACCCAGGUCCCUGUUCCUCCUUUUCCAGAGCAAACACUGCUAAGGGAUCAUGACAGUCCCUGCAUCUGGCCCAGACUGGGCCUUGGGAGGCUUUUGACAUCAAUCCAUGCAACCGCACCCAACAAUUGGAGUCAGCAUGGGAGGUGAGACCCACUUGCCAAUUUUGCUCUCAGGGAACAGCCCUCUUUACUAAAACAUAGCACAGUAUUGAUAACAGUUGUUUCCAGGCAUCGUAGAAAGCGUUUAGUGGGCAUUAACGUCUUUGAUCCUCACCACAAGGUCAGGGGUUGGAUGAUGUUAGCAUGCUCAUUGAAGGAUCAGAAAAGUCAGGCUCAAGAUAGCUCGCCCUUCAUUCAGCCAGCCGGUGUUAACUGAAUAUUAACUGUGCACCCGUCUGUGCCAGUGUUCCCCCAGGAGCUGCAGAGGGUCCUGAGCAGAGUGAGCUCAAGCCACUUGGGAGCUCACAUUCCAGCUAUCAGUGCUGAUUCAUCUCAAAUGUUUGAUCCACGCUGGGUUCUAACCCUUCCCUGCUCAGAGCCCUCAGAGUCCAGGUCAGGUAGAACCCAGAACAGAGCCUCUGGCAGGAAGGAGCUUGCAUGGUCCUCAGGCUUCAUGUCCAGAGAUCAUUCCUCCACUUUGAGCUUCUUUGUGAAAACCAAUCACAAAGAGAGGAGGGGUGAAAUGUGCCAAAGCCUCUGCCAGGGUUGUAGCAAGGAAACCUGGGCUUCUAGGGAAAGUUGAGAAAGGGCCUAUAUUAGUCAGGAGGGCUACUGUAAGAGAGUACCACAGGCUGGGUGGCUUAAACAACAGAAAUUUAUCACCUUACGGUUCUGGAGGCUAGAAGUCUAAAAUCAAAGUGUUGGCAAGGUUGGUUCCUUCAUGAGGAAUUUCUUGGCGUUGCCUGGCAUAUAGAUGCAUCACUGCAGUCUCUGCCUCGUUGUCACAUGGCCAUCUUCUCCCUGUGUCUAUAGGUCUAUGUCCAAAUUUCCCUCUUCUUAUAAAGACACCAGUCAUAUUGGCUUAGGCCCAGCCCAAUGAUUUCAUCUUAAUUUGAUUACAUCUCUGCUAUGGUUUGAAUGUGUCCCUUCCAAAAUUCAGGUUAUUGCCAAUGUGAUAGUAUUGAGAUGGGGUCCUUAAAGAAGUAAUUAGGCCAUGAGGGUGCCUCUCUCUGAAGGGAGGCUCAUUGGAUUGUAUCAGUGUAACAUAAUUUACAUAACCAGUUCUUUAUGUGAUGGAAAUCCCAUUCAACGGUUUCCAACCUUUGCUAUUACAAACUGCUGUGAAGAGAAACAUAUGUCAUUAUACUAAUCAGGUGCUGUUGUUGUUUUUAUAAUGCAUUAUCCUGGAGAGACUGCCCCUCCCAGGGCUAGCUACUUUGGGGAGAGAGUAAACAACUUGGUCGAGCGUGCCUUUCGUAUGCAAACCAGUCAAUCCAGAGCCCACACCCCCAGUCACCUCCUUUAUCAAACUCUGACACAGCAAGCCAAUAUUCCCCCUGCCCUAAAUCACUCCAGGGCCAGGCAUGGGACAACUAGGGACAAUCCCUAUAGCCAGGGCCUGCCAAAGUUAUACAGAUUAGCCAAUCCUAAGCCUGCUUCCCUGCCUUGCCUUGCCUUUCUGCUGGAAACUACAUUAAAGGCGCUGGAUCGUGCUUUUCCCUCACCCCCUCUGCUUCUUGGCUGACCCAAGUUCUUCCUGUGUGGCCCUGCAAGGCGUGACACACCUCUCCUCCUGGGAACUGCAUAACAAACUCUUCUUGCAGAGAUAGUUUUCUCUGUGUCUGUCAUCUUACCAUACCUGAUGAAAACAAAUAUGGGUACAUUUUUUUUUUUUUUUGAGAGAGAGGGUCUCACUCUGUCUCCCAGGCUGGAGUGCAGUGGUGUAAUCACAGGUCACUGCAGCCUCGACCUCCUGGGCUCUAGUGAUCCUCCCACGUCAGCCUUGCAAAUAGCUGAGACUACAGGCACACACCACCAUGCCUAGCUAAUUUUUGGUGUAUUUGUUAUAGAGACAGAGUUUCGCUAUGUUGCCCAGGCUGGUCUCAAACUCCUGAGCUCAAGUGAUCCACCCACCUUAGCCUCUCAAAGUGCUGGGAUUAUAAGUGUGAGCCACAGCAUCCAGCCAUGGGUACAUUUUAAAGCAGGCGUUUUGUUCAUGUGCAGCCCUUGUUCUCAGUUAAGGGGAAAAUGAGUGAUCCUUUGCUUGGCUCUGAAGGAGCAGUGUUUUAUAUGUAAAGAAUAUAUUCUGUAUAUUUAAAGAAGAGCAAUGGGGGGCAUUUGAAAAUAAAUCCGUUCAUUUUUUUCUGAUUGUAAAAAUAAUAUAUGCUCAGUAAAGAGAAUCUGAAAAAUACAGAAGUAUUGGGGGAACCCACCCCCAAUAUUUCAACAUAGGUUCUUUCUAUUUUCCAUAAGUGUCGGCCGACUGAGAAAUAAAGAGAAAUAGUACAAAGAGAGGAAUUUUAACAGCUGGGCUGCCGGGGGUGACGUCGCAUAUCAGUAGGACUGUGAUGCCCACCUGAGCCUCAAACCAGCAAGUUUUUUAUUAAGGGUUUCAAAAGGGGAGGGGGUGUAAAACAGGGAGUAGGUACAAAGAUCACAUGCUUCAAAGGGCAAAAGCAGAACAAAGAUCACAUGCUUCUGAGGAAACAAGACAAAAGGCAAAACAGAACUACUGAUAAGGGUCUAUGUUCAACUGUGCGCGUAUUGUCUUUUUUUUUUAUUAUUUAAGUUUUAGGGUACAUGUGCACACUGUGCAGGUUAGUUACAUAUGUAUACAUGUGACAUGCUGGUCGCUGCACCCACUAACUCGUCAUCUAGCAUUAGGUAUAUCUCCCAAUGCUAUCCCUCCCCCCUCCCCCCACCCCUCAAUAGUCCCCAGAGUGUGAUGUUCCCCUUCCUGUGUCCAUGUGUUCUCAUUGUUCAAUUCCCACCUAUGAGUGAGAAUAUGCGGUGUUUGGUUUUUUGUUCUUGCGAUAGUUUACUGAGAAUGAUGAUUUUCAAUUUCAUCCGUGUCCCUACAAAGGACAUGAACUCAUCAUUUUUUAUGGCUGCAUAUGUGUAUAUGUGCCACAUUUUCUUAAUCCAGUCUAUCAUUGUUGGACAUUUGGGUUGGUUCCAAGUCUUUGCUAUUGUGAAUAGUGCCGCAAUAAACAUACGUGUGUGUGUGU